AGUCGCCGCGGCGGGGUCGAGCGGGGGCGGCAGCUGACAGGCGCUCCUCCCCCGACCGCAGCGGCUGGUUCCCAGCGAGGCGGGCGGCCCCCAGCUCGCGUCCCCGAGUCCUAGCCCGCGAGGCGCCAGGGCUGCGCCUGGGCAUGGAAGAGGGGAAGAUGGACGAGAAUGAAUGGGGGUACCACGGAGAGGGCAAUAAGAGCCUGGUGGUGGCCCACGCGCAGCGCUGCGUCGUGCUGCGGUUUCUGAAGUUUCCUCCAAAUAGGAAGAAGACCUCGGAAGAGAUAUUUCAACACCUGCAGAACAUAGUGGACUUUGGGAAAAAUGUCAUGAAGGAGUUUUUGGGGGAGAACUAUGUUCAUUAUGGGGAGGUCGUUCAGCUACCUUUAGAGUUUGUGAAACAGCUUUGUUUAAAGAUACAAUCUGAAAGACCAGAGUCUCGCUGUGACAAGGACCUGGAUACUCUCAGUGGUUACGCUAUGUGCCUUCCUAAUUUAACCAGACUCCAAACCUACCGCUUUGCAGAGCACCGGCCGAUUCUGUGUGUAGAGAUUAAGCCAAAAUGUGGGUUUAUUCCUUUCUCGAGUGAUGUCACGCAUGAGAUGAAGCAUAAGGUCUGUCGAUACUGCAUGCACCAGCACCUCAAGGUAGCAACUGGGAAGUGGAAGCAGAUCAGCAAAUACUGUCCCCUUGAUCUCUACUCAGGAAACAAACAGAGAAUGCACUUUGCCUUGAAGAGUUUGCUGCAGGAGGCACAGAACAACUUGAAGAUAUUUAAGAAUGGUGAGCUGAUUUACGGCUGCAAAGAUGCCCGGAGCCCCGUGGCUGACUGGAGCGAGCUUGCACACCACCUGAAGCCGUUCUUCUUCCCUUCCAACGGCCUGGCCAGUGGGCCCCACUGCACAAGGGCUGUGAUCAGGGAGCUGGUGCACGUGAUCACACGGGUGCUGCUGAGUGGCUCGGACAAGGGCCGGGCAGGCACCCUGAGUCCGGGGCUCGGGCCUCAGGGCCCGCGAGUCUGCGAAGCCAGCCCUUUCAGUAGGAGCCUUCGCUGCCAAGGAAAAAACACCCCAGAGCGCUCGGGGUUACCGAAGGGCUGUCUUCUGUACAAAACCCUCCAGGUGCAGAUGUUGGACCUGCUGGACAUCGAAGGCCUCUACCCUCUGUACAACCGGGUUGAGCGAUACCUGGAAGAGUUUCCCGAGGAGAGAAAAACCUUACAAAUAGAUGGGCCUUAUGAUGAAGCAUUUUACCAGAAGCUGCUUGACCUUUCCACUGAGGAUGACGGGACAGUGGCCUUCGCGCUAACGAAGAGUUUCAUUUCAUCGUCCAGGCUGGAGUGCACUGGCACGAUCAUGGCUCACUGCAGCCUUGACCUCCUGAGCUCAGGUGCAGCAGUACCGCGUCGCCAUGACUGCCAAGGACUGCUCCAUCAUGAUUGCACUGUCUCCCUGUCUGCAGGAUGCCAGCUCUGAUCAAAGGCCUGUCGUCCCUUCAUCGAGGUCCAGGUUUGCCUUUUCCGUGUCUGUGCUGGACCUUGACCUCAAGCCCUACGAGAGCAUUCCCCAUCAGUAUAAACUGGACGGCAAGAUCGUCAACUAUUAUUCAAAGACUGUACGUGCCAAAGACAACGCCGUGAUGUCGACUCGGUUCAAGGAAAGCGAAGAUUGCACAUUAGUUCUCCACAAGGUCUAACUCUUUCCCUGCAGUGUCUUUGAAACUUGAACAUAAUGUGAAGGCUGAAUGAUAGAGAUAUUUUCUGUUGUGUUGGGUGACCUUUGGUUGUGAAUGUUUUUGCUUUUAACCCCUUUUGAGGUGGGAUUGCCUCUUGGAGACAUGGAAUUGAAGAGCACUAGAAACAACUUCCUGGACAAGGAAUGUAGGAAGUGAGUGCUGUGUCCCAGGAAGCUGCUCACACUCUUAAAAUGGAAGUGUCCGUUAAGCCCUGGGAAGACGUUCUGGAUAGUUCUUCUUUCCCAACCAGGGCUCAUGUCUGAUUCUCUAAUGCGAAAAGCCUUAUUCUAAGACCCAAGGUUUGGAUCUGCUACCACCAGACUCCUAACAUAGAAAACUUGAAUUGUCACAUACAUUUUACAGUUUGGACUUUUAAGAAAACAUGGAUACUACUGGAACUUCCCCCAGCUGAGUUACAUGGUCACUUUUUCAGUGCAAGCCACAUAUCAACACAGGUUUUUAGGUGGUUCCCUGCUGCACAGCGUGACCUCGUGGUCGCGCAGAUGCCGAUUCUGAGCAGUGUAGACUCAGGGUCCCUGUGGAGGUGCUGAAGCCCACAGUUCCACACAGGGCAGCAGGGAGCGCAAGGCUCAGGUCAGGAUGGACACCACUCAUGCGAGCAUUGACCUUUUUUUUUUUGCUUUACAAUUUAAUCUUUCACAUGAGGGGGAGAUGAGCUGUUCUUUCCCACUAAAAAUUGCUGCUGUAGAAGUUGGAGGUGGAGCUGUGACUGGCUGAGCUGCUGUGGCCGGGCUGGGCAGUGUGCCCCAACAGCUCAGUGCUUUCCUGACACUCCAGUGUCUGGGGUGGUUGAGGAGCGAGUUCUCUCUUCCUCCCAGACCAAGUUCCUCCCUCGGGUUUGCCUUGAGACGUGUUGCGUUUUUGGGCCCCGUGGCCUCUCCCUGUUAGGCUGCCACAGGCCCUGCUUCUGGAAGGUGAACAGCUCCUGGCUGCUGCCGAGAGGGUUCUCGUUGGGGUCACCAAAGUGUGCCCGGCUGCUAUGAAAAACGUUGGGAAUCUUGGUUUCAGUUUUUUAUUCUAUGCUAGGUUGUACAGACUUAUUUAUAUCAUCGUUUUGAGGGACUAAUGGAGGCUUAUUGUAACAUAUAAUAUUAGUGAAACCAUGGAAUUAUAUGAAAAUGAUACAUGAGAAAUAAGGAAACUAUUUUGCUGAUUGUAAAUUUUUGUGGGAAAUUUUGUGAUAACUUGAGAAUUAUACUUGUUUGAAUCAAGGCAACUCUUCUAGAAUUUAUUGUUCAAUUCUGUCAUAUUUACUUCUAAUUCUACUCUCAGAGGUGCAAAAAGAUACUUAUCUAACUGGACACUUUUACUGUUUUCUUCUCACUUCCAAUGACACCGUCUCAUACACACGGGUCCUGUGUGCUGGGAUGGGGGCUUUGGUGAAGUGCACGGAGCUCACGGACAAGCCGCAGGCUCUGGGAAGCGUGGAGGUAGUGGCCGUUGAGUACUGUCUUGACCCAAGGGAGUUCACUGUUGCUGGGCUGGGGCUGGGGCAGCCUGGUUUGGGAUGAUUUUGCCCAUUGUCACGGUGUGUGGAGGAUGCUGGGUCCUGGGUUCAAGUGCACAUGUGAGGGAACCCCAGUCCGUGGGAAGGUGGGCUGGGCUCCCUAGGUCCUUCAGGGCUGCAAGAGUUAUUGCCUAGCACAGGGCCCAGACAGGGCUGGACUAGACACGAUGAAAACAGCCUGUAUUUGAGGGAGAAGAGAAAACAGAUGGAGACCCCCACUCUGUCUGGUCUUGGCUCCCACCAGCCCGGGCUGUGAGGAGCCCCUGAGCCGCGGGUGCCACUGCUGUGGAUGCGUUUCUGGCCCGUCUUGGAAACUGCUGCUGCUGCGUAGUCAUGACGGCCCUGACUGGUUUGAGACAACACGCGUUCACAGAUCUUAACAAUGCUAAAUGGGCGACUGAUGAGGUCACGGUUCUUAAGGCACAUCCGGGACGAUCGAUAUAGCACUUAGGCUAUGCAGGGGGGUCUUUCUUUCAUAAAGGACCUCAUUCCUUGCGUCCCAGCCCAGGAACAGUGCUGUCUUUGCUGUCUUAGGCCAUUCUUGUUAUUAAGCUGACAGCUUCACUUUCUUGUGGAAGACCAAGAACAGCAUGAGGACUUGCUGAGACUGCCUCACGGUGCCACCAUGCGGACCGGGGGGAGGCAGGGAGUGAGGGUGUGGCUCCCCUGGGCUACUAAGGACAGUUUAAAGAUGAGGCGCCAUAGGCAUCCGUCUCCAGAGCCCCCAGGAGGCAGGAACCAGGAUAAGGGUGGCUUCUCCCAGCUGAGUAAUGUGGCCACCAUGUCCAAGGUGGACUCGGUGUGAGGCUGCAGUGGGUGGGGGAUGGAUCCUCCCCACACAUCUGAGGACACACAACCACUUGGUACAUUUUCUCAGAUGUUAAGCUUAUUUUUAUAAACCACAUUGUACGUGUCACUUUUAUUUGGCAUUUUAUACUUAACUAGUUGUAUUUAUUUUUCAUGUCAUGAGAGUUUCCAUAUAAUGUGCCAUAACUGCAUAGACAGCACGUCUUCAGGGUGUGGUUUCUAAGCAGAAAAUAGCAAAUGUUUAUAUUGAAUAAAAUUGCAUGUUCCUCCACGCA